AUGCCCAGACCUGGAGGAUCCCCAGGGUCUUCUCAUGGUUGCAGCAGGAAGGACACCUCUCUGAGGAAGAGAUGGCCAGAACAUUUAACUGUGGGGUUGGCGCUGUCCUUGUGGUAUCAAAGGAGCAGACAGAGCAGAUUCUGAGGGAUAUCCAGCAGCACAAGGAAGAAGCCUGGGUGAUUGGCAGUGUGGUUGCACGAGCUGAAGGUUCCCCACGUGUGAAAGUCAAGAAUCUGAUUGAAAGCAUGCAAAUAAAUGGGUCAGUGUUGAAGAAUGGCUCCCUGACAAAUCAUUUCUCUUUUGAAAAAAAAAAGGCCAGAGUGGCUGUCUUAAUAUCUGGAACAGGAUCGAACCUGCAAGCACUUAUAGACAGUACUCGGGAACCAAAUAGCUCUGCACAAAUUGAUAUUGUUAUCUCCAACAAAGCCGCAGUAGCUGGGUUAGAUAAAGCGGAAAGAGCUGGUAUUCCCACUAGAGUAAUUAAUCAUAAACUGUAUAAAAAUCGUGUAGAAUUUGACAGUGCAAUUGACCUAGUCCUUGAAGAGUUCUCCAUAGACAUAGUCUGUCUUGCAGGAUUCAUGAGAAUUCUUUCUGGCCCCUUUGUCCAAAAGUGGAAUGGAAAAAUGCUCAAUAUCCACCCAUCCUUGCUCCCUUCUUUUAAGGGUUCAAAUGCCCAUGAGCAAGCCCUGGAAACCGGAGUCACAGUUACUGGGUGCACUGUACACUUUGUAGCUGAAGAUGUGGAUGCUGGACAGAUUAUUUUGCAAGAAGCUGUUCCCGUGAAGAGGGGUGAUACUGUCGCAACUCUUUCUGAAAGAGUAAAAUUAGCAGAACAUAAAAUAUUUCCUGCAGCCCUUCAGCUGGUGGCCAGUGGAACUGUACAGCUUGGAGAAAAUGGCAAGAUCUGUUGGGUUAAAGAGGAAUGAAGCCUUUUAAUUCAGAAAUGGGGCCAGUUUAGAAAGAAUUAUUUGCUGUUUGCAUGGUGGUUUUUUAUCAUGGACUUGGCCCAAAAGAAAAACUGCUAAAAGACAAAAAAGACCUCACCCUUACUUCAUCUAUUUUUUUAAUAAAUAGAGACUCACUAAAAACAAGACUAGUUAGUGCAGCAUAUCUGAGACA